AGCAGAGUAGACUCUGUCCUGGGACUUGGUGGUGCUACCCUUGGCCUCCCACAGUCCUGCCACCCUGCUGCCGCCACCAUGCUGCCCCCUGGGACUGCGACCCUCUUGACUCUGCUCCUGGCAGCUGGCUCGCUGGGCCAGAAGCCUCAGAGGCCACGCCGGCCCGCAUCCCCCAUCAGCACCAUCCAGCCCAAGGCCAAUUUUGAUGCUCAGCAGUUUGCAGGGACCUGGCUCCUUGUGGCUGUGGGCUCCGCUUGCCGUUUCCUGCAGGAGCAGGGCCACCGGGCCGAGGCCACCACACUGCAUGUGGCUCCCCAGGGCACAGCCAUGGCUGUCAGUACCUUCCGAAAGCUGGAUGGGAUCUGCUGGCAGGUGCGCCAGCUCUAUGGAGACACAGGGGUCCUCGGCCGCUUCCUGCUUCAAGCCCGAGACGCCCGAGGGGCUGUGCACGUGGUUGUCGCUGAGACCGACUACCAGAGUUUCGCUGUCCUGUACCUGGAGCGGGCGGGGCAGCUGUCAGUGAAGCUCUACGCCCGCUCGCUCCCUGUGAGCGACUCGGUCCUGAGUGGGUUUGAGCAGCGGGUCCAGGAGGCCCACCUGACUGAGGACCAGAUCUUCUACUUCCCCAAGUACGGCUUCUGCGAGGCUGCAGACCAGUUCCACGUCCUGGACGAAGUGAGGAGGUGAGGCCGGCACACAGCUCCAGUGCUGAGAAGUCAGUGCCCCGAGAGACGACCCCACCAGUGGGGUGCCCGCUGCCUGUCCUCCGUGAAACCAGCCUCAGAUCAGGGCCCUGCCACCCAGGGCAGGGGAUCUUCUGCCGGCUGCCCCAGAGGACAGUGGGUGGAGUGGUACCUACUUAUUAAAUGUCUCAGACCCCU